GGGCGUGUAUCCGCGGCCGUAGCAGCCGGGCUGGUCCUGCUGCGAGCCGGCGGCCCGGAGUGGGGCGGCGGCAUGUACCUUCCACAUUGAGUAUUCAGAAAGAAGUGAUCUGAACUCUGACCAUUCUUUAUGGAUACAUUAAGUCAAAUAUAAGAGUCUGACUACUUGACACACUGGCUCGAGCAAACAUGAACGUUGGAGUUGCCCACAGUGAAGUGAAUCCAAAUACCCGUGUCAUGAACAGCCGGGGUAUGUGGCUGACAUAUGCAUUGGGAGUUGGCUUGCUUCAUAUUGUCUUACUCAGCAUUCCCUUCUUCAGUGUUCCUGUUGCUUGGACUUUAACAAAUAUUAUACAUAAUCUGGGGAUGUACGUAUUUUUGCAUGCAGUGAAAGGAACACCUUUCGAAACUCCUGACCAGGGUAAAGCAAGGCUCCUAACUCAUUGGGAACAACUGGACUAUGGAGUACAGUUUACAUCUUCACGGAAGUUUUUCACAAUUUCUCCAAUAAUUCUAUAUUUUCUGGCAAGUUUCUAUACGAAGUAUGAUCCAACUCACUUCAUCCUAAACACAGCUUCUCUCCUGAGUGUACUAAUUCCCAAAAUGCCACAACUACAUGGUGUUCGGAUCUUUGGAAUUAAUAAGGGGAACAGCGAAGCCAGAUGAUUUAUUAGUUAUUGCCGGUGAAAAUACAGAGAUCCUUUGAAACAUUUGUCUCUCCUAGAAUUCUCAUCAAACCAUAUGCUUCUAACACAGCACUUAACAGUCAUGGGGAGUAUGUGGGAAUAACAGAGACUCGCUUCCCUGCCAAAACCACACAUAGACCCACACACUUGAAAAAUAAGGAAAUAAGAUCAUCUGAGUAUGGAGAUUCCUCAAAAAUUAAAAUUAUAUCCAGCAAUUCCACUUCCGGGUAUAUACCCAAAAGAAGUAAAAGCAGGAACUUGGACAGAUAAUUUGUACAUCUAUGUUCACAGCAGCAGCAUUCACAAUAGCCAGAAGGUGGAAGCAAUCCAAGUGUCCAUCAAGGGAUGAAUGGUUAAAAGAAAUGUGACAUAUACACACAAUGGAAUAUUACUCAGCCUUAAAAAGGAGGAAACUUCUGAUAUAUAUUACAUCUUGGAUGAAUCUUGAAGACUUUAUGAUAGGUGAAAUAAGUCAGUCACAAAAUGACAAAUACUGUGUUACCCCACUUUUAUGAACUCCUAGAAUAAUCAAAUUUAAAGUGGAAUGGUGGUUGCCAAGGGCUGGAAGGCAGAAGGAAUGGGAGCUUAUUGGUUCUUGUUUUUGUUUUGUUUUUUUUUUUUUGAGACGGGAGUCUCCUUCUGUUGCCUAGGCUGGAGUGCAGUGGUGCAAUCCCAGCUCACUGCAACGUCUGCCUCCCAGGUUCAAGUGAUUCUCAUGCCUCAGCCUCCCACGUAGCUGGGAUUACAGGCAUUCAUCACCACAACCAGCUAAUUUUUGUAUUCUUAGUAGAGAUGGCCAUCAUGUUGGCCAGGCUGGUCUCGAACUCCUGACUCCAGGUAAUCCGCCCACCUCAGCCUCCCAAAGUGCUGGGAUUACAGGCGCGAGCCACUGUGCCCGGCUGGGAGCUUAUUGUUUAAUGGGUACAGAAUUUCAGUUUGAGAAGAUGAAAAGGUUCUGGAGCUAGAUGGUAGUCAUAGUUGCAUAGCAAUGUGAAUGUACUUAGUUCCUUUGAACUUAAAAAUGGUCAAAAUGGUAAAUUGUUAUGUAAAUUCUACCACAAUAAAGUUCAGAAAAGUUAAUUUGUAAAAUAAGCAUAAUGGUUCAGCAAACAAAACCCAAAAUAUCUUCCAAAGACCUGAUUGACAGUAUUACCACUAAUGAAAGAACGUUCCACAUCAAGAGAUACUGGUCAGCAAAGAAAAUUUAAGAGGAGAAAGGAUGGGCUGGGCGUGGUGGCUCACGCCUGUAAUCCCAGCACUUUGGGAGGCCGAGGCAGGUGGAUCACGAGGUCAAGAGAUGGAGACCAUCCUGGCCAACAUGGUGAAACCCCGUCUCUACUAAAAAUACAAAAAUUAGCUGGGCGUGGUGGCGUGCACCUGUAGUCCCAGCUACUCAGGAGGCUGGGGCAGGAGAAUCGCUUGAACCCGGGAGGCAGAGGUUGUAGUGAGCCAACCUCACACCAAUUGCAAUCCAGACGUCGUCUCAAAAAAAAAAAAAAAAAAAAAAUGGAGAAAGUAAAAUGGCAAUGUAUUUUUAGCACUAGCCAAGUCAAAGAAUGUAAGACAAUGUGACUCAAGUGGAAAGGGCUGCAUCAGGCUUGAAAUACUAGCCAUUAAAAGCACCACACACAUUUCUAUUGUUUCUGUUCUGUAUUUACCAAGCAAUCUUCUGAUUAUAAUUUGGAUUUAGCCUUCAUUGUAAUUUGGUCAAUACAAGGAAGAUAAUGACCAGCAAACUCAACUAUCCUAGCUUCCCCAUAAUUGUGUUUCUCAUAAAUAAUACAUUAGUAUUAAUGGCUUUUACACAGCAUUUUAUUAGCAGUUUGUGGUGGGUAACUCAGUACUCCAGAGUCCAGUCACUUCCAGACCUGAUAAACCAAUUUCAAGCCUAUAAAAGAAUCAGAUAUUGAAACUCAAGUAAUCACACUAUGGGCCUGCCAGGCUGGCAUACAUCUGUGGCACGCCAAUGUGGCUUUUCCCAAGCAAUACCCCUCUCUGAAUGCAGUUUCCAUUCACAUUUCCAUAAUUCUGUACUGCAUUUUGUCUUCUGCCUGUAGACUCAGAUUCUUGAGAACAGAGAAUGGACCUUAUCUGUAUCCUUAUACUAAUAAAGUUCCUAGCAUAAAGGAAAUAACCCAAUAAAUAUGUAACAAAUGAAAAUAAAACCUAACCUAGUAGGACAUAAUUAGGAAAUAAAUAUUGAAAAAUAGGAUUUGGGCCAGGCGUGGUGGCUCAUGCCUGUAAUCCCAGCACUUUGGGAAGCUGAGGCAGGUGGAUCACGAGGUCAGGAGUUCAAAACCAGCCUGGCCAACAUAGUGAAAUGUCAUCUCUACUAAAAAUACAAAAAUUAACUGGGAAUGGUGGCAGGCACCUGUAGUCCCAGCUACUCGGAAGGCUGAGGCAGGAGAAUCGCUUGAACCCCGGAGGUGGAGGUUGUAGUGAGCUGAGAUGGCACCACUGCACUCCAGCCUGGCAACAGAGUGAGACUCCAUCUAAAAAAAAAAAGAAAGAUUCUUAUAUGUUUUAAUAUAUAAUAUGUAUUAAUAAUAAAAUUUUCCUCUGAAGGCUACAAAUGGAAAGCUAGACACACAAUAUCUGAGACCAAAUAAGCAUAUCUAGAUUCAGCUGGAACUCUCGAUUUAUGUUGAACUUACAUAGGCCAUAUUUUUUGAGAAUGCCCAUGAGUGGCAUUCUAACUAUCUGCAUAAAAGUACAGACAGGCCUCAGAGAGCAUACAUGCCUUUCCCCCAAUAACCCUCUCCUAUGUUACAAUAGAGAACAUAAAAAAUGUAUAUCUUUGCUAAAUACAUGGGACUUGUAUAAGUGCCACUUUACAUAUAUUCGGUCAAGGGAAAGAUAAAAUUCCAUACUAAUGUGCCCUAGAGUUCUCCUGUUUCACAUAAUAACAGCAUUCGGACUCAACACUGGCCAAGAGUGCCUAGACGAGGAAUCUACCAAUGAUAGCACACACAAUAGGAUCUUGCUUGUCUUGACAGCACAGAAGAGCAUUGGGAUAUACUUGCUGAACAUAAUUGGAAUUGUAAGAAAAAUAAUACCUGAUGUGAAAGGUUUUAUGUUCAAACUGGAUUCCAGUGUAUAACAGAAAUAAGCUCUGACCUCUCUAACCGUAUGACUAAUUUUUCUUAACUUUUAGGUUUUAAUUUUUCUUUUUUCCCUUGUUUAGGCCAACAGUGCACCCUAGAGAAAAUGUGAGUUAUUUUCUCUUCUAGCAGUUAAGAAAACAGACUCCAGUGCCAGAUGUCCUGACUUCUAAUCCUAGCUUUGCUUUUCCUAGUUGUGUGACCUCCAAAGCACCCAAACUCUGUGGCCCAGUUGCCUGUAAAAUGAGGACAGAAACUAUUUCAUGGGAUUUUGAAAGAAAUUAAUCUACAGCAGGUGCCUGGUACAUAGUGCCACUUUAUCAUUAUUGUUACACAUAAAUGAAAUUUUUGAAAAACAUAAGUUCCAAAUAAAAAACCUCAACCAUA